AGAGGACCGGCAGCCGGCGUCGAGGCGGGGCGCGGGAACGACGGCGGCCAUGGCGGCCUCGGGGCCCGGGUGUCGCAGCUGGUGCUUGUGUCCCGAGGUGCCAUCCGCCACCUUCUUCACUGCGCUGCUCUCGCUGCUGGUUUCCGGGCCUCGCCUGUUCCUGCUGCAGCAGCCCCUGGCGCCCUCGGGCCUCACGCUGAAGUCCGAGGCCCUUCGCAACUGGCAAGUUUUGGAAAUACUCAACAAAUAAUGAAGUACUCUUCAGAUAAUGAAGCCUCUGGUGAUGGCCAGACUGAGCCACUAUGGAAGGAGGGGUCAGGAUUACAGCAGAGGAGACUGGCACACAGAGUGUUAAGUGACACCCACUCAAUCCACCCCGAAGCUGUUACACUUAAUUAACCCUCAAACUGCCCAGUGAGUUUACAGGCUGGUAACCUACAUCUUUGUCUACGAGAAUCCCAUCUCCCUGCUCUGCGGCGCUAUCAUCAUCUGGCGCUUUGCUGGCAAUUUCGAGAGAACCGUGGGCACCGUCCGCCACUGCUUCUUCACCGUGAUCUUCGCCAUCUUCUCCGCUAUCAUCUUCCUGUCAUUCGAGGCUGUGUCAUCACUGUCAAAGCUGGGGGAAGUGGAGGAUGCCAGAGGUUUCACCCCAGUGGCCUUUGCCAUGCUGGGAGUCACCACCGUCCGUUCUCGGAUGAGGCGGGCCCUGGUGUUUGGCAUGGUUGUGCCCUCAGUCCUGGUUCCGUGGCUCCUGCUGGGUGCCUCGUGGCUCAUUCCCCAGACCUCUUUCCUCAGUAAUGUCUGCGGGCUGUCCAUCGGGCUGGCCUAUGGCCUCACCUACUGCUAUUCCAUCGACCUCUCAGAGCGAGUGGCACUGAAGCUCGAUCAGACCUUCCCCUUCAGCCUGAUGAGGAGGAUAUCCGUGUUCAAGUACGUCUCAGGGUCUUCAGCCGAGAGGAGGGCAGCCCAGAGCCGGAAACUGAACCCGGUGCCUGGCUCCUACCCCACACAGAGCUGCCACCCUCACCUGUCCCCAAGCCACCCUGUGUCCCAGACGCAGCACGCCAGUGGUCAGAAGCUGGCCUCCUGGCCCUCCUGCACCCCCGGGCACAUGCCCACCUUGCCUCCGUACCAGCCUGCCUCCGGCCUGUGCUAUGUGCAGAACCACUUUGGUCCAAACCCCACCUCCUCCAGUGUCUACCCAGCUUCUGCGGGCACCUCCCUGGGCAUCCAGCCCCCCACGCCUGUGAACAGCCCUGGCACGGUGUAUUCUGGGGCCUUGGGCACACCAGGGGCUGCAGGCUCCAAGGAGUCCUCCAGGGUCCCCAUGCCCUGAGAGAAUUUCUAGGGAAGUCAUCUCACUUGGCCUUCUGAAGGUCCUCCCUAAGAGUCUCCUGACAAAAGUUACUUAUUGAACACCUCUAUGUGCCAGGCUCUGUGUUGGGUACUUUGAUCAAUGCCCCUGUUUCAGUCUCAUCUGUACUCACGGCAGCCCUGUGGAGUACGGUGUACUGGCCCAGCUUACAGAUGCAGAAAGCGAGACGUUCUGCCAUCAGAUAAAGUCACGUGGCUCUUUAGUAACACGGACAAGGCUCCUCGCCAAGGAACUCGUGGCAGAAGAGGGCAGCAGUUGGCAGUAGCUGCCGAUGUCUGUCCCCAGCUCCACCAUUCCUCCCUGUGGCUGUGCCGUGCUCGUGGUUUCAGUGUCCGUGUGUCCAUGUGUCUGCCCUUCAGGAGCUCGCAGCUGGUGUGCUUGGCGGUCCCAGGCCUGUGUAGUGUCUCUCCCCUGCUGCGGGCGCCCCCACCCCGAUUCCUCUCCCCAGAAGCGGUGGGAUGGGCCCCCAUGAACUGCAGCAGCAUGCUGAGGUGUCCAUGUUGUCUGCCUUUGUAUAAAGAAACAGCCUCUGACCUGC